ACUGUGCUGUCACUCUGGAAUUCUGCUGUGUGGGAGCUGAGGCCCCACCUGCAGACCUGCUGCUCACCUGGGCAGGUGCCUCCUCACAGCCCAUCUGCACAGCUGGCCUGCGGAGUCCUCCUCAGGGGCCACUGGCCCUCACCUGCCACUGUUGAAGGGAUGCCUGCCCCUGCUCUCCCCACCUCAGCCAUGGCCGUGCAGGUGCCCCUGUGGCACCACUACCUGCAGGCCAUCCGGUCCCGGGAGGCGCCGCGUGCCCAGGACUUCCAGCGCGCAGAGAACGUGCUGCUCACGGUGCUGGAGCGCGUGCAUGCCCUGGACCCCCGCUUCAUCGUGGACUACUCCCGUGGCCUGGAGGCCUUCCAGUUCGCCCUGCGCUCCUCUGAGGACCCAAUGGACAUGGAGGUGCCCCUGUGGGUGGAUGCCGAGGCUCUACUGAUUGAGGAACCAGAGGCCACCCAGCCGGAGGAUGGCCUUGAAUUAUGCCACCUGGGUGUGCCCAGGGAAGGGGCUGGCCUGGAGCGGUGGACCACCGAGGAUACCUUCACUGCCUCCUCGGAGGGUGACGCCAAGUGCCGUGGACACAUUGUGCCCAGCAAGGUCCUGUGUGUCCUCAAGGACCUGCUGGUAGCAGCCAUCGUACACUGCAAGCACCACAGUCUCAUCGCACCAGGUUCGCUGAACGCGGCCAGCCUGAGGGAGGAGCAGCUCCACCUGUCCUUGCUGGUGUCCAGCGGCUGGAGAACAAUCAGCUUCCACGUGGUGCCCGUGGUGAGAAGGAAGCUUGGGGCGCCUGCCCUGGAGGGGGUGCAGCAGAUGCCCGGAUUCCCUGAGGGCAGCUUGAGAAGGAUCCUCAGCCAAGGGGUGGACCUGGUGCCGGCCAGCGCCCAGCUCUGGAGGACCUCCACUGACUACCUGCUCACGAGGCUGCUGGGGGAGCUGGGCUCCCUGCAGGGUCAUCGCCUGGACAGCCUCUCCAUCCUCGACCGGGUCAACCACGAGAGCUGGCGUGACAGUGGCCAGACUGACGGCCUGACCUUUGGCCACCUGAAGAUGGUGCUGCUGUGGGCCUCUGUGCUCUUCCUGGCGCCCGAGGACUGGGCAGAACUGCAGGGCGCCGUGUACCGCCUGCUGGUGGUGCUGCUCUGUUGCCUGGCCACGCGGAAGCUGCCCCACUUCCUCCACCCGCAGCGCAACCUGCUGCAGGGCAGCGGCCUGGACCUUGGUGCCAUCUACCAGCGCGUGGAGGGCUUCGCCAGCCAGCCCGAGGCGGCCCUGCGCAUCCACGCCACCCACCUGGGCCGCAGCCCCCCGCCGCGCAUCGGCUCCGGGCUCAAGGCGCUCCUGCAGCUGCCAGCCAGUGACCCCACUUACUGGGCCACUGCCUACUUCGACGUCCUGCUGGACAAGUUCCAGGUCUUCAACAUCCAGGAUAAGGACCGGAUCUCUGCCAUGCAGAGCAUCUUCCAGAAGACCAGGACUCUGGGAGGCGAGGAGAGCUGAGCUGGGCCACCUGGUCUCAGCCACCUGUUCUUGGCUCCCCAACAGACUCUGCACUGCACCAUGGGAGGCUCCUGGGAUGUUUGGAAGAAGAAACGGGCUUCUCCUUGAGGGGGUAGUGGAGGGAUUUUGUCCCCAGCAGUGGCCUCUGAGAGUCUUUCAGUGCCUGGUGGGGCAGGGCAGGCCUCUUGGAGCACCUCCUCCCUGGGUCAGGGCCUGGAUGCAGGUGCCAAGCUCUCCAUGUGGUGCAUGUUGACCCAGCCACGUGGUGUUGUCAAGCAAACAGCAUCGGCAGGAGACCUGGAGCUGAGGACUUGGCCCUGCCUGCACUGUAUGCCAUUCCUUGGUGACGAAAUGCUGUAUAUUUGGUUUUGAAAAAAUGAAUGUGCUGGGUAUACACAGCAGAAAGGGUACUGUCCACUUUUUGUAUAUCAGUGUGGAAAAUAUUUCCCCUAGAAGUAGAAAAGGCUCAUGUGCUGAUGGAUAAUUUUGAGUCUUCUCCAUUCUCUGUGAAUGACCCCCUUCCCCAGGCAUCCCCACCUCCUACCUCGUUCUUAGAGCAAACUAAAGCCAACUGAGGGUGCACACACAGCCAUGAGCCCACCUGCCCAGGACUACUCCCAUCUGCUUCUUCCCGUCCCCGUGGAAGUGGCCCCUGAUAUGGAUUGUAUCUGUAUCCCCACCCAAAUCUCAGGUAGAAUUGGAUCUGUGUCCCCACCCAAGUCUCAGGUAGACUUGUAAUCCCCAGUGUUGGAGGAGGGGCCCAGUGGGAGGUGAUUGGAUCAUGGGGGUGGAUUUCUCCCUUACUGUUCUCAUGAUAGUGAGUGAGUUCUCAUGAGAUCUGGUUUUUUGAGUGUGUGGCCCCUCCCCCUCUCCUUUUGCUCUCUUCCUCUUUCUCCGGCCAUGUAAGAUAUGCCUCCUUCUCCUUCACCUUCCACCAUGAUUGUCAGUUUCCUGAGGCCUCCCAGCCAUGCUUCCUGUAUAGCCUGCGGGACUGUGAGUCAAUUAAACCUCUUUAUUCAUUA